AAUCUACAUUUUGAGUACCCAUGAACAAGAUGGAAUUCUGUCAGAUACUGUGGCUUAUGGGCUAGACAUAGUCUGUGCCCUUGGAUAAUACAGUACCUGAAGAGAUGGUUAGAUGAUAAGAUGAAAAAUAAAAUAUAUACACAGUUCUUAUAUAUCAUUGAAACCAUGAUAUAUGAAAGGAAACCAUUCUUUAUCAUUGACCUAUUGAAGAUCCUGGGUAAGUUCCUUUUAAUUUUUGUGCCAUGCUCCUUCUUUGCCUUGUCCUGUGAGGUCCAGAGAAGAUGAGGAAAGUGAGACUAGUAAAAUGUGUUGGAGGUUUCUCAUAAAAGUAGUACUGUAAGAAUGUACUUGGAAGUUAAUAUUUUUAAAUGGUUCCAUAUCUCAAAUCAAGCAAUUCAUAUUAAAGAUUUGCUGAUUGAGCUCUUAAAACAAAAAUUUGGCACUUCACUGUCAUCUAAUGGCAUUCUAUCUUAAAAAAAAUUCUACCUUAUAUUUAUUUACUUCUCAGUUUGAAUCUUCUUCAAGUGCACAUUCUUAAUCUCAAACCUCAUGUAGAGAAUUAUUUAUUUAGAUGUUUCCAAACUGGUUUCUUGGCAUAGUUCUUGCAUGGUGUGAAUAAAUUCUUCAGAUAAGGUCUUUCGUGACCCACUGUGACGUUCUGACCUUCAUUCUUGUCAUUCUUCAACAGACCUCAUUGAGAACUGCAUAGUUUUUGGAAUAUUGUGACUUUUAAUCUGUAAGCAUGGUAACUGUGGCAUAGAAUCCCUGUAUGGCAGUCAUUCUUAAUCUGUUUGGGGUUAUGUAUUACUUUGAAAGAUUGAUAAAAAUAUAUGGAGUCAUUUCCCAGUAAAACGUACAUAUAUUCUGUCACAAAAUGUUUUGCAUGAAAUUUCAGGGGGUUUGUGGAAUUCAUUUUACCCCUAGGACCCAACUUAAGAACUGUUUUGUCCAACAAUGUUUCUUGACAUUUAAUGUGCAUGGGAAUCACCUGGGAAGCAUAUUAUAAUGCAGAUUGUGAUUAUACAGGUUGAGAAUGAGUCUGAGUCUGCAUUUUUUAACAAGGUCCCUGGUGAGGAUGGAGCUCCUGGUCCCUGGAGCACACUUGGAGUUACAAGACGAUAUGGAAACAUGACAAAGCUUUUUUAGUAUAUACAUAAAACAAACAAAUGAAUGUUUGGGUCUUCUAUUGUUUUUUUUAAAUAUGAUUUAAACUUUUUUCUGGCAAUAAAUACAGUACUUGAAGAGAAAGUUAAGUUUGCUUUCUAAAAUCUGUUGCUUAUGUAUUACCAGCAUUUUAAAUAAAAUUUUAUAAUUCUAGUUUAACAAGUUUAGGUACUUUCUUUACUCUGUGAAGAACUUUUUACCCUUUCCUGUGCUUUCAAUGCAAAUAUACUUAAUACAUUUUUUUCAUUGAAUAACAUUUUAAGGCUAUUACUGUGUCUUUAGCUUAAUGAUGCAUAAGAGGAGAUCAUGGAAUAAGGUGGGUAGGAAAAGCUAAACACCUAGAACAUGGAUCUACACAUGGUAAAUAGACAGUUAAUACAUUGUUAACCUGAAAUAAAGUUUGUACUAGAAAUGGGAAAAGCUUAACAGCCUGGGGAACUGAGGAUGAAGUCUCAAAAGUAAAUUGUCAUUUUGAAUGAAAAAACAACUUACAUGUUGAACCAUCUGAAGGAAUCAGUCUUUCUUUUUUUCUCUUCCCCACCCUCAGCUUAUUGAAGUUUAAGAGUCAGUCUCUUAAUGAUUGCUGAAGGGUGUUAUAAAGAAACGUAUUUCUAGUAAAGUUCUCUAUUUUUAUUUUAUUAUUGGCUAAGCUAAUAAAAGAGUCACAAGAUGAGGUUUUUUUUGUUUUAAAAAAACUAAUCAUAUAUUAAGGUUGGACUAUAUGAAGCUGCUGAUAUUUAACCAUUUCUGAUCAACAGCUUAAUUCAAUUGAUUAAAAAAAAAAGAGGGAGUGAUGAGGCUUCACUAUGUUGCCCAGGCUGGUCUCAAACUCCUGAGCUUUCAAGUGAUCCUCCUGCCUUGGCUUCCCAAAAUGCUGGGAUUACAGGCAUGAGCCACCAUACCCAGCCAAUUCAAUUGAUUUUUAAUGGAAAUAUGAUUUAGGAAAUUGGGAUUGAAAUCACCCUGUGGGCAUAUGCAGGUGUUAAUGUUCUUCUCUAAAUAUCUAGAUAGAACUUAAAAAAAAUCAGAAGUAGUUAACAUUUUAGAUUGAGAAUGUAUUUAUGGAUCUAGACUCAUCAGGAAUAUCAAUUUUGAGAUAUUUGAAGAUAAAAUGCAAGGAAGCCCUCAAGAUAACAUAUUAGUUUUGAGAAGGAGGGUGAUAAUAUCUACUGAGAAUAGGCUUGUUGUGAGGAUUGAAUGAAAUAAUGUAUAUAAUGCCUUUGUCACAGUCCUUGUACAUACAGGACUAUCAGUAUAUAAUAGUUACUGUUGUGGCAUUAUGACCAUGUGCUUUUUUGAAUAAAGGUGAACUAUAAGUUGAUCUAAUUUUUGACAAUGUAUAUUUGCAUGGACUGAUGAACAUCAUCUACUAUAAACAAAAAAAAUCUGCUGAAAUAAAGCAGUAUUAAGAAAUAGUUUGAAAAAGCAGGGCGUAUUUUUUCUACUUUGUUUCUAGGUUACUUCAGAGCUUCUGCAUUCUUAGAAUACUUCAUUGAUACCACAUUUAUGACAUGUCACAUAUUCUAGUGUGUACCUCUCUUAAUUUAUUUACCAACUGUUAAGGAACAGUGGUAACCAUGUCAUCCACACCACUUGUCAUAGAGUAUGGGUCACAUAAAUAUUUGUUGACCAAAUGAUUCAUGUCAGAUUUAUCUCUCUAGAUUUUGGUGUCUCUUUUGAAGUAUAGAAUCAACAGGAGGGAAUUGUUAAUUUAAAUACAAAUGCCAUGUAAUAGAAAGCCUUCUGGGAUGUCUUGAUUAUUGUUGUGCUGUAGUAAUUUUGAAGUAAUGAGAUGUAUUAAUUUGCUAGGGCUACCAUAACAAAAUGCUGGAGAAUGGGUGAUUUAAACAAAAAUCUGUUUUCUCACAUUUCUGGAGGCUGGCUGUCCAAGAUCAAGGUUCCACCAGGGUUAGUUUCUCCUAAGGCCUCUCUCCUUGGCUUGCAGAUAGUUGCCUUCUAGCCGUAUCCUCAUACAGUUUUUUUCUUUGCUUACAUCCUCUUUUUAUAAUGUGUGUCUUCCUCUUUUUAUAAGGAUACCAGUCCUAUUGAAUUAGAACCCCAUUCUUAUGAUUUCAUUUAAUUUUAAUUACCUCUUUAAAGGCCCAGUCUCCAAAUACAGUCACAUUGGGACUAAGGACUUCAACAUAGGAAUUUGCGGGGGAGCACAAUUAUAGUCAUAACACAAUUUAGUCAUAACACAGGGUGUUUGGAAAGUAUACAAAAAAGAUUUAUUUUAGAAUGUACAAGCUUUUUUCUUUGUGGUAUUGGGACAAAUUAUGUAAUUUCUCUCAGCAUCCCUUUUCUUACCUAUGAAAUAGUGACAAUAAUUAUGUCAAAUUGCUUGUAAAAAAAUAGUGGUUGUGAUAUUUGACCCAAAUUUCAAAAUAUUGAUUGUAAAACUUUCUAUUGACAGUAAGGUAACAGAAAAUGAAGAUGAUUCCUUGAUAAGUUAAAGGCUACUUUAGAAGUUUAGAGUUUAAACUUAAACUUAAAUAAAGGCUGCCUUUAGAAGUUUAGAGUUUAAACCAGAGGUUGCAGAUUGGCAACCGAUGGGCCAGAAACAGCUUGCAUACUGGUUGUUGGCCUACACAAUGCUUAAAAAUUUUUAAAUUAGUUGCCAACUUCUGCAGGUCAAUUAGAUUCACAUAAAAAUCUAGAUUUCUAAUUUAGUUUUUUCUAAGCAUGGUAGUAAUAGACUGGCCUUGAGUAGCAGUGUUGCCGUCAGGGAUAUGGUUUAAAUGUGAUGACAAAAAUAUAAUACUGCUUAUAUUGGGUGUCUAUCCAAAAAAAUGGCAAAAUAAAAAACAGACUGACGGGGCCACACUGAUGUGAAAAAAAAAUAAUGUUGUGCUUUGUAAAAAUAAGUAAUAGUCCUUGAUAUUUCAUAUACAAAGUAUGUCUAUUAAGAGAAUAUGAUUUAAAAUUGCCAGCAUCCAUCACUUAAUCCCAAUACCCAUUGACACCUGUAGGCUUUGAAUUUUAACUUCUUAAUGAAAGCUGGCCUAUUAAGGACAUAUGCAGUCAAAAGUAGGUGCCCAUAUAUAUAAUGAAAUACCAAAAGGACAAUUUAGAAGGUUGAAUGGAAACAUUAUGGCAUGCUUUAGACGUUCUGUUUUGGUUUUCUUAUUCCCAGUCUUUGAUCUUUUAGGUCUAUCCAUUGGUAAAGAUAUAUUAGGACUCACAUCAACUCAAGGUUUUUUUCUUUUUUUUUUUUUUGUGGUGAUAGUGUAAGUGCCCUGUUAUUUUGAAAUCAUUUGCCUCAGUUAUAAACUUCUACCUCUCUUUUCAGGUCUUGUAGAAUUUCUCUUUUAUAUUCUCAUUGAUUAUUCAAAAAACUUCACCUUGCACUAAGUUGCUAGUAACUGCAACUGUGGAAUAUAAUCCUUUACCCCCUUCUUCUUGCCAAGAAUGCCUUAUUCUACUUUUAUCUGAAGGACCCCUCAAUUUUACCUCUUCUGUAAUAGCGUCUUUUAAAAAUUUUCUUUUACUUUUGAAGAAGUUUACAUCUUCAGAAAAGUUACACAUAUGGUAUCCAUAUACGCUUCACUUAAAUAGUCCACUUAUUAAAACUUGACGCUUCCUCUCUCUGAAAAAUUUGAUUUUGAAAGAAUAGGUGUGUGCGUGCGUGCGUGUGUGUGUAUGUGUAUGUUUCUUUUCUCUCCCAAAACUGAGCCAUUUGGAAGAAAGUGGCAUGCAUCAUUCAUAAUAUUUGGAACUCCAAAUACUGUAAUCUGUGUUUCCUGACAAUGACAUUCUUCUACAUAAGUAUAAUACAGUGAUUACAUCAGGAAAUUUCACAUUGAUGGUGACACUGCCACUUAAUAUACAACCUUUAUACAACUAUCUCUAGUUGUUCCAAUAAUGUUCUUUCUAGCAGAUUUUUUUCCUUCGUUUUUUUCCUUGCAGCCACAUCAAGACAAAUUUUACACAUUGAUUUUUAUGUCUGUUUAGUCUCCCUUAAUAUCCAUCUGUUCAGGUACAUCUCGUUGUAUCCUCAUGACUAGAGUCAGGUUAAUCAUUUUUGGCAGGAAUAUUACAAAGGUAAUAUUAAGUUCAUUUCAUUGCAUCACAUCUGGAGGCAUACAUUGGUUAAGAUGGUGUUCACUAGAUUUCUUCACCAUAAAGGUACCCGUCCCACUUUGUAAUUAGUAAUACAUUAGACCAUGUGACUAUCCUGUUCCCUAACAGCUUGUUACCCACUGGUUUUAGAACUCAUUGAUGCCACUUUCUGGAAUCAUAUGUUACUAUAGUUGUUAUAAGAUGCUGUGAUUUUCUAUUUUUAUCAUUUCUUUCACAUUUAUGAGUCAGCAUUCUUCUAUAAAAAACUUUCCUUUUCUCCCCUUAUUUUUUGUAGUGUUAGUAUGGGCACAUGGAUAAUCAUUUUAUAUACAAUGAGUUAUAUUCCAUCUUGUCUUUCAUUUUCAUUUUCCACUUGUUCCAAAUUAUCCAUCCAGUUUUUGAGCUCUGCUCUUUUCUUUAAUUUCUCUUCUUUUCCACAAGAAACUCCAGGUUCUGCCCUAGCCCUGGCAUCAGCCGUUUCUUCAGAGAGUUCUAAUUUCUUUUACUGGAGAAUGAUAUUUAGAAACUAACAUGGGCAUUAGGUAUACCCCUUUUGUGGACAGAGCUAAGAAAUACACCUGCUACAUUAAUGUGUAGACUUAAAAAAAAUAAAUCACGAGUUAAAGCUAGUACUUCUAAUUCCAAUCUAAUGUAGUAAGUCUUUUCUGUCAUUCUGUAUUUGUAUUUGCAAAUAUUCUGGUUUCCAGAGUAUCAGCAUAUUUAAUCUUUUGGAUAAUUAUAUAAUACCCAGAAAAUAGUUGCAGAAUUAUGCAAAUGUCACUAAAAGCAAUAAAGUUAUUAAGUUCAAGAUUUCUUCACAGUUCUUUUGAUCCUACAGUGUAUCCCACUAAAUCUGUAUAGUUCAGAGUACUAUGUUCAAACGCUUUUGGCUAAUUUUUUUUUCUUCUGUUUGAUUGUUACCAAAUUGAUAUAUAAUUAGGUUCGUUUGUUUCUUUUUGUAUUAUUUUUUAGGGUUCAACUAUCCUUAUUUAACUUUUUGACUAUUUAAAAUAUGAACAUGAUUCAAAGGCAAAACUAUAUAAGAAGAUAUAUUCAGUGAAAUCCCAUUCUCAUCCUUAUCCUUUCCACACUGCUCCUACCCACCUUUUGUACCUGGGGCCCAAGAUUUGGUGGAUUUCUCUCCAGUUUAUCGAUGUCUACAUAUAUAUUCUGUCCUGGGUGCCCGGGAAACAUUUGAGAAUUACUACCGAAAACAGAGGCGAAAACAGGCUCGUUUGGUACUUCAACCUCCAUCUAACAUGCAUGAAACUUUAGAUGGCUACAGGAAGUAUUUUAAUCAAAUUGUAGGCUUUUUUGUGGUUGAAGAUCACAUUUUACAUACAACCCAGGGCUUAGUAAAUAGAGCCUACAUUGAUGAACUGUGGGAAAUGGCACUUUCAAAAACCAUCGCAGCACUCCGUACCCACUCGUCUUACUGUUCUGAUCCAAACCUUGUGUUAGAUUUGAAGAACCUCAUUGUGCUUUUUGCUGACACACUUCAGGUGUAUGGUUUCCCUGUAAAUCAGCUUUUUGACAUGCUGUUAGAAAUCAGAGACCAAUAUAGUGAAACUCUGCUAAAGAAGUGGGCAGGUAUUUUCAGAAACAUACUUGAUUCUGACAACUACAGUCCUAUACCAGUAACAAGUGAAGAGAUGUACAAAAAGGUGGUAGGACAAUUCCCAUUUCAAGAUAUAGAACUGGAAAAGCAACCAUUUCCAAAAAAGUUUCCUUUCUCUGAAUUUGUGCCAAAAGUUUACAACCAAAUUAAAGAAUUUAUCUACGCUUGUCUGAAGUUUUCAGAAGAUCUUCAUCUAAGCUCAACUGAAGUUGAUGACAUGAUUCGGAAAUCAACAAACCUGUUGCUAACCAGGACUCUGAGCAACUCUCUGCAGAAUGUAAUUAAAAGGAAGAAUAUUGGGCUUACUGAGCUUGUUCAGAUUAUUAUCAAUACAACACAUUUGGAGAAAUCCUGUAAGUACUUGGAAGAAUUUAUCACCAACAUCACUAAUGUGCUUCCAGAGACAGUUCACACUACCAAGCUCUAUGGCACCACAACUUUUAAGGAUGCUAGACAUGCAGCUGAAGAAGAGAUUUAUACCAACUUAAACCAGAAGAUUGACCAGUUCCUACAGCUGGCAGACUAUGACUGGAUGACCGGAGAUUUGGGCAACAAAGCUAGUGAUUACCUGGUAGACCUCAUUGCCUUUCUUCGUAGCACCUUUGCUGUAUUCACACACCUUCCUGGAAAGGUGGCCCAGACAGCGUGUAUGUCAGCUUGCAAGCAUUUAGCCACAUCCUUGAUGCAACUUUUGUUGGAAGCUGAAGUGCGGCAGCUCACCUUGGGAGCAUUACAGCAGUUCAACUUGGACGUCAGAGAAUGUGAACAGUUUGCCAGAUCCGGCCCGGUGCCUGGGUUCCAGGAGGACACGCUGCAGUUGGCCUUCAUCGACUUGAGACAACUUUUGGAUCUUUUCAUCCAGUGGGAUUGGUCAACCUACCUUGCUGACUAUGGUCAGCCCAACUGCAAGUACCUCCGGGUAAACCCAGUGACUGCUCUGACCCUGCUUGAGAAGAUAUCUAGAGAGAUGAAGGAUACUAGCCGCAAGAACAACAUGUUUGCACAGUUUCGGAAAAAUGAGCGAGACAAGCAGAAACUCAUUGACACCGUGGCCAAGCAGCUCCGAGGACUCAUCAGCAGCCACCACUCAUGAAGGGUGACCCCGGACCCACAGAGGCGACCUGCUGCAGCCUCUGUGUCAGUCUGGGGUCCAGCCCCAGCUGACCCUGCAUUUGUGCAUUCUUCUUCAAAGAGAGCAUAUGUAUUUUUUUAUUAACCCCUGUGCAGUAUUCACAUAACAUUUCCCUAUAGUAAAAGAGGCACAAGAAUAAGCAAGUACAUGAGAUGUUGCUAGGCUGGGACUCAGGGGAAGUUAUUACUACACUAUCUGUGUUAUCUUAGAGAUGGUGGUAUCAUCAAUUCCACAGUGAUGAACCACCUUUCAUCCAUGGCUCUAAAGCUUAGGUCUGGGGCUUAGGAACCAUAAAAAGUGGGUAUCUGGCGCUGGGAGGUAGAGUGAGUAAGCAAAAGGAUACUAAAAUAUGUCCUGUUCACUCUUGGAUGCCCAUUCACCACAUAGAUGAGGCUGAUUCUUCUCAAUACAAGGAAAGGGCAUGGCAAACAUUACUAUUUAGUACACUAAGGGCAGCUCUGGAGGGUCAUCUCCUCAGUCUGCUGACUUUCACUGGCUUGUGAACAAGCAUGGCAUAUGGCAAGAUGACAGCUUCAUUCCAAUCCCCCAAGAAUGGCGGUUUCUUUAGCCUGAUCUAACCCCAGGCUUUUAUUGCAAUUUUUUCUAGGGCAGGAUACAGCUAAGUAGACAGCAGUAAUAAUUGGAUCCCAUGUUUAACUGCAUAUUGCCCCAGCUCUAGGAGUGUUGAGUCUCAACUCGAAGAGUUUUUCUGGAUCUUGAAAGCCAGUUUUCAUGGAAUCAGAGACCCAAUCCCUUCCCUGUUCAUCUCAUUUCCUUCACUUACAGUCAGAGCACUUGGUUCAGGACAUAAAUCAACAGUUACUUCCAUAGGCCUUCACAGGGCGUUUCAGACUUAGCCUCCUCCAGUAAUGCCAUUGAAAUAGUUCAGAUUUCGGAAGCCUAAAAAUGGCCUUUACCUUACCCUUAGGUGUAACCUGAGGAUUAGUUGGGAUUGUUCCUUUAUGUUUUAAAACCAGCUUUUUGGUUAUCAUCUUUAAGGAAAUGUCACCAGCUCUGCACUGUGGGGGCAGCCAUGCCUGGACUGGAUGCCUCUAGGGAUGGAGACAUUGUUACCAUAAAGUCGACAGAGCCAACCAUGGCUUGUGGCUUGUUGCCUCUGGCCCAACUGUCCUUCACUAAAUAAUAUCCUAGAUAUUAUUUUGUUGCUCAAGCCCAAGGUUCCCACCCUCUUUUGAGAUCCCCAAAGCCAUCUUUGGCCUUGUCUAAGAAAGAUUGCCUAUAAUCCUGUCCUCCAAACUCUAAAGCCUGGAGCAGCUUAGCGUGGAGGCUGCACUCAUUGACCCAGAUGGACUCCUGAGACUUAACGCAAGGGCUUUGCUAUGAGGUCAGUCGGGGGAAACUGUACUUUAAGACACUUCAGAAAGAUGCUACUGGCUAGUAGCAGAAAGAUGGCUAGUGGCAAGAGUAUAAUUGUGCAUCACCAAACAAUGACAAAUAAGCCACACAGGCAUUUCCAGCUUGGAUUGAUGGGAGGAGAGACUCAUCAAACAGAAUUCUUCACUACCUUUGUCAGCUACUGAGUUGCUUCUGGGGAGGGAAGUACUUCCUUGCCCCUCCCCAACCCCCCUACCUCACCAUAUCCUAUCAUAUCUUGAUAGUCAUGGGGAAGAGGAUGUGCACACAGACAUACAAAUUUCCUCAAAGCUGGAGAGACCAGGCUACAUGUGAGCUCAUAGAUGCUGCUGAGGCUCAUCCUGAGGGCUGGAUGGUUGGCCAGGGUUUCAGAAUGAGGGUAAGGGAUGAGCACUGCCACCCAGAACUUGAUAAGCCAAGAGAAGGCAGGAGCCAAAAUGGCAUCGCCAAGCUCUCAUCUUUGUUGAAACAAGUGAGAAACGAUUAUAUUAAUCUGAAGUUCUAUUGCUUGAGAAGAGUUCAAAACACUUCUCUUUGCUAGUACCCAGUUUGCAGCAAGAUCUCUUCAGCUUUAAGUGCUGAGAGACUUUGAAGUGGAAAUGGAGAGAUGUGUAAGCAUGGCACAGUGUUUGUCUUUUUAGAGGAUCAUCAUUGCUGGUCUGGUCUCAAACCUCUGCCUUGGAAGAACUGUGCUAUACAGGAAAAAGUGAACAAGGUGGAGGAAUAGGGGUUAUUCUGCACAGAAGUCCCAUGAAAGGAAAAGCUUAUUCAAGCUCAAGACAUAAAGAUGGACCCUUUGAUAUAUCUUCUCUCCAUUCUUAGUCUGCCUUCACCUUAUCUAACAAAAAACAACAUGCAGCUACUGAGUUGUAUGUAGAGACAUACUCUUGGUGGGCCAGGGAAGGUAAAAACAGGGACCAGCAAUGUCAAGUUUUUGAACUAGAAAAGUGGGAUGUUUUUAGUUUUGUCUAUAACCUGUAGCUGGGCCAACCCUUGAGAGGACUUGUGCAAAGCAUGUGUGCCCAGACCCAUCAGACUCCUCAGAUAUGGCCUCAAAUACCUAGAGAUGUAGAAGUACCGUGGAGGGCCUCAAUAAGAGGGCAAGCACACAGAUGGCUAGAAGCCUGUAUGGCUUCUGGUCAGGAUGAACCCUUGGCCAAGUUCUUGAGGAAACCAGGUCUAUAUUCCUGAAGGGACAGUUCAGUUUGGGACUCUAUUAGGUUUCAGUAGUAAUAUAGGCUGCUUGCAUCAUUUUAACAUUCAUAGGGAAAAUCUCUUUGAGCAGGCUAUAAAUGAAGCUGUUGCAGGUAGGGAAGAACAGGACCUGAAAAUGGGAACCAGGAAGUGAGAUCCUGUUGGCAAAGGGAAUGUAGAGCUUCCAGGGUGCAUUGCCCACUGUUCUCAUUGCAUACCAGUCCUCCAAGUCAGUCUAGCCUUACUGUACACUUGACAAGUGCUUACUCAGCAAGUCCCAGACCCACGGCCUUUUAUCUCCCAAGACUGGCUUUGGCCAUGACCUUCCUCAUCAGGCCUCUGAGCACACUCUCUAGGAACUGCUGCAGAAAUUCCCCUACCUUAGCCUCCCUUCUCCCAGGACUCCUCUCUUGACUGCAAUUGCCUCUUCUUCUUCUUCUUCUUCUUCCUUUUUGUUUUUUUUUUUUUUGCCUGCAUUCACAAUUACUUUUCACAAAGGUGUUGGAAAUGGCAUUUUUAUUUUACACAGAUAGUUGCACAUAUAUAGAGAAAAUUAGGAAAGUCCAUUUUUAACUCUAAAGGGAACUUUUUUCUCUAAAACUUACUUGUAAAGCUACUGAUACAGAUGGGCCGCAUGGUUAGGGGAAAGCUCCUCUGUGAAAAGAGCAUGUUUAUUCCUCUUGUACAUUUUCCUCUUUUAACUGCUAUUAAACAAGAAAGCCUACAUACCUGUUUCAAAAGCCA